AGAGUCGGAUUCGCCGCCGCAGCAGCCGCCGCCCCCGGGAGCCGCCGGGACCCUCGCGUCGUCGCCGCCGCCGCCGCCCAGAUCCCUGCACCAUGCCGUCGGAGAAGACCUUCAAGCAGCGCCGCACCUUCGAACAAAGAGUAGAAGAUGUCCGACUUAUUCGAGAGCAGCAUCCAACCAAAAUCCCGGUGAUAAUAGAACGAUACAAGGGUGAGAAGCAGCUUCCUGUUCUGGAUAAAACAAAGUUCCUUGUACCUGACCAUGUCAACAUGAGUGAGCUCAUCAAGAUAAUUAGAAGGCGCUUACAGCUCAAUGCUAAUCAGGCCUUCUUCCUGUUGGUGAACGGACACAGCAUGGUCAGCGUCUCCACACCAAUCUCAGAGGUGUAUGAGAGUGAGAAAGAUGAAGAUGGAUUCCUGUACAUGGUCUAUGCCUCCCAGGAGACGUUCGGGAUGAAAUUGUCAGUGUAAAACCAGAAAAAAUGCAGCUCUUCUAGAAUUGUUUAAACCCUUACCAAGGAAAAAAAAGGGAUGUUACCAACUGAGAUCGAUCAGUUCAUCCAAUCACAGAUCAUGAAACAGUAGUGUUCCCACCUAGGAGUGUUAGGAAGUUGUGUUUGUGUUUCAAGCAGAAAAACUGAGCUCCAAGUGAGCACAUUCAGCUUUGGAAACUAUAUUAUUUAAUGUAGGCUAGCUUGUUUUCAAAUUUUAAAAGUUUAAAAAUAAAAUACUUUGCAUUCUAAGUUGCCAAUAAAAUAGACCUUCAAGUUAUUUUAAUGCUCUUUUCUCACUAAUAGGAACUUGUAAUUCCAGCAGUAAUUUAAAGGCUUUCAGAGAGACCCUGAGUCUUCUCUUCAGGUUCACAAAACCCGCCGCCUUUUUGGGUAGAAGUUUUCUACUCAGCUAGAGAGAUCUCCCUAAGAGGAUCUUUAGGCCUGAGUUGUGAAGCGCAACCCCCGCAAAACGCAUUUGCCAUCACAGUUGGCACAAACGCAGGGUAAACGGGCUGUGUGAGAAAACGGCCCUGACUGUAAACUGCUGAAGGUCCCUGACUCCUAAGAGAACCACACCCAAAGUCCUCACUCUUGCAGGGGUAGACAUUUCUGGUUUGGUUUGUUCUCUAGAUAGUUACACACAUAAAGACACCACUCAAAAGGAAACUUGAAUAAUUUAUAAUUUUGAUCGAGUUUCUUAAAAGACCCUGGAGAAAGAGUGGCAUUUCUUCUGUUUCAGGUUUUGUCUGAGUUCAAACUAGUGCCUGUGUUGUUACGGAAAGCAGCAGUGUACCAGUGUCACUCUGGAGUACAGCGGGAGAAACACAAAAUAGUAUAACUGAAAACAUUAACAUUCAGACACACUCCCUUCUGCCUUCCGGCUUAAAGCUGUGGAUGAUCCACGUUUUUGUUUUUUUAAUGUUAAAUGUGUAACUCAGUAUUACUGAAAAGGUACCCACAUUUUGAAUAGUAGUUAUCACUCUUAGGUCAGACAGCCAUCAGAAUUCUCCCACACCAAGUGCAUGUCAGUUGUGGAGAAAACAUAGCAAAAAGAGCCGUACGCUCUUUACAGAUACUAAUGUCAAGAGUUAAACCUCCUCAGGUUCAACCUGUGAUAAAAGACUAGUGCUUCCCAGUACUUGCAUGGGGUUCACUAUUUAUAGUUUUCUUGGGAGUAUCACAGGAAAAUCACAAUUACACCACUUUAGACCCUAUGUGUAGCAGGUCACAACUUACCCUUGUGUGUUUAGAUGUGUAUGAAAUACCUGUAUACGUUAGUGAAAGCUGUUUACUGUAACGGGGAAAACCAGAUUCUUUGCAUCUGGGCCCUCUACUGAUUGUUAAAGGAGUUCCUGUCACCUGCUCCCCCCACCCCCGCAUGCGUCUGUCCACUUGGCUAACUUUUAAUAUGUGUAUUUUUACAUUAUGUAUAUUCUUAACUGGACUGUCUCGUUUAGACUGUAUACAUCAUAUCUGACAUUAUUGUAACUACCGUGUGAUCAGUAAGAUUCCUGUAAGAAAUACUGCUUUUUAAGAAAAAAAAUAACAUGCUGAGGGGUGACCUAUAUCCCAUGUGAGUGGUCACUUUAUUUAUAGGAUCUUUAAAACAUUUUUAAUGAACUAAGUUGAAUAAAGGCACAAUUAAAAACUGUCA